GUCUGCUCCGGGAGCCCUGACCCGAGUCGGAGCUGUGUGUCGCAGCCGCCCCGACCCCCCGCCGAUCAUGCGCCGGCGCCCCUGGCUCUCCAGUCCCACUGGGCUGUGAGCCCCCCACUCCCAGCCCGUCAGGGCCUGCGCGCCAUGGGCAGCGCCCACCCUCGCCCCUGGCUGCGGCUCCGACCCCAGCCCCAGCCGCGGCCAGCGCUCUGGGUGCUCCUGUUCUUCCUACUGCUGCUGGCUGCUGCCAUGCCCAGGUCAGCACCCAAUGACAUUCUGGACCUCCGCCUCCCCCCGGAGCCCGUGCUCAAUGCCAACACAGUGUGCCUAACAUUGCCAGGCCUGAGCCGGCGGCAGAUGGAGGUGUGUGUGCGUCACCCUGAUGUGGCUGCCUCAGCCAUACAGGGCAUCCAGAUCGCCAUCCACGAAUGCCAACACCAAUUCAGGGACCAGCGCUGGAACUGCUCAAGCCUGGAGACUCGCAACAAGAUCCCCUAUGAGAGUCCCAUCUUCAGCAGAGGUUUCCGAGAGAGCGCUUUUGCCUACGCCAUCGCAGCAGCUGGCGUGGUGCACGCCGUGUCCAAUGCGUGUGCCCUGGGCAAACUGAAGGCCUGUGGCUGUGAUGCGUCCCGGCGAGGGGACGAGGAGGCCUUCCGUAGGAAGCUGCACCGCUUACAACUGGAUGCACUGCAGCGUGGUAAGGGCCUGAGCCAUGGGGUCCCGGAACACCCAGCCCUGCCCACAGCCAGCCCAGGCCUGCAGGACUCCUGGGAGUGGGGCGGCUGCAGCCCCGACAUGGGCUUCGGGGAGCGCUUUUCUAAGGACUUUCUGGACUCCCGGGAGCCUCACAGAGACAUCCACGCGAGAAUGAGGCUUCACAACAACCGAGUUGGGAGGCAGGCAGUGAUGGAGAACAUGCGGCGGAAGUGCAAGUGCCACGGCACGUCAGGCAGCUGCCAGCUCAAGACGUGCUGGCAGGUGACGCCCGAGUUCCGCACCGUGGGGGCGCUGCUGCGCAGCCGCUUCCACCGCGCCACGCUCAUCCGGCCGCACAACCGCAACGGCGGCCAGCUGGAGCCGGGCCCAGCGGGGGCACCCUCGCCGGCUCCGGGCGCUCCCGGGCCGCGCCGACGGGCCAGCCCCGCCGACCUGGUCUACUUCGAAAAGUCUCCCGACUUCUGCGAGCGCGAGCCGCGCCUGGACUCGGCGGGCACCGUGGGCCGCCUGUGCAACAAGAGCAGCGCCGGCUCGGAUGGCUGCGGCAGCAUGUGCUGCGGCCGCGGCCACAACAUCCUGCGCCAGACGCGCAGCGAGCGCUGCCACUGCCGCUUCCACUGGUGCUGUUUCGUGGUCUGCGAAGAGUGCCGCAUCACCGAGUGGGUCAGCGUCUGCAAGUGAGCGGCCCGGGGUCCCCUGGGCCCUGAUCGAGGUCCCCUCCUGGAGCCUGGCCCUCUGAGGCUUACGGUCUUGGCAAGGCAGCAUCGCCUUGGCUCUUGGGAAGAGGAGAUUGGACCACAUGAUCUUAUAGGAACCCCUCAGCUCUGAGGUCUGUGAUCGCCGGACAGUCCAGGCCUGUCUGAACCCCACCACUCACUUCUGUGGGCUCUAGGACUGACUGGGUUCUUCCUCCCUCCCCGAAGCCCAGACAGUUCAGUUGGGCUGGGGGUUGCUCCACACCCUAAAACAAGCCUCAGCCAGGCAACCCGUCAGUCUGUCUCCAUCCUUUCACCCCUUCCCUGGAGAUGGGAGGUGGGGAAUGAAUGGAAGCUGACGGGCAGAGAGAGGAGGAUUAAAAAAAAGAAAUAGACAUAACUGAGCUGAAGUAAUUCCAUAAAGGGCCCAGACAGCCUCCUCCACCAUUCCCUUCAUCAUUCAUUUAACAAAUAUUUAUUUUGCACUCUCUUUGCGGCACUCUGGGGGCGGUGGGGUGCGUGGGGGUGGCAAUGCAAGGCACUGAGGCCACAGAUGUGAGUAAGCGAGACACAACACUUGUCCUCUUGGAGGUUACAUUCUUGCUGGGGGGAGGCAUGGGCAAUAAACAAGUAAAUAUACAAA